AGAAGUCAGCCUAACACCCACAGAGAUUAAAACGUCUCUUCCUUCCUCUUUGUUUCCACGUCCCAGUCUUCAAUAAAUUCUAUCUGACAACAGCAGCAGAGGGACCCACUAUCUUGUGGUUUCUGUCAAGUUCCUGAUUUUCAUCCGUAGUUGAAGAUGAGCAAGAACUCUGUAACAGUGUUACCUUGGAGCCUACAAUGAGAGGUAUUUCAAAAUGAGUGAAGCAUGACUCUCACAGAUGAAGGCCUAGACGCAGGAUUUCCAAUCGUGGCUGUCAAAAUAUAUCUGUGAUGAAGAGAUAUCAAGGAAAAUGUUUAAAAGGAUCUUUAAUGAAAAAACACUUGGGCCACUUCAAGACGACAAACGCUCACUGGGCAAAACACCUUCACUGAAAAGAGACCUCAUAUUAUGCAAAAAAAAUCUUAAAAGGCCUCUGCCUUCAGAAGUUACAAGAUGAUCAAUUCAACCUCCACACAGCCUCCAGAUGAAUCCUGCUCUCAGAACCUCCUGAUCACUCAGCAGAUCAUUCCUGUGCUGUACUGUAUGGUCUUCAUUGCAGGAAUCCUACUCAAUGGAGUGUCAGGAUGGAUAUUCUUUUACGUGCCCAGCUCUAAGAGUUUCAUCAUCUAUCUCAAGAACAUUGUUAUUGCUGACUUUGUGAUGAGCCUGACUUUUCCUUUCAAGAUCCUUGGUGACUCAGGCCUUGGUCCCUGGCAGCUGAACGUGUUUGUGUGCAGGGUCUCUGCCGUGCUCUUCUACGUCAACAUGUACGUCAGCAUUGUGUUCUUUGGGCUCAUCAGCUUUGACAGAUAUUAUAAAAUUGUAAAGCCUCUUUGGACUUCUUUCAUCCAGUCAGUGAGUUACAGCAAACUUCUGUCAGUGAUAGUAUGGAUGCUCAUGCUCCUCCUUGCUGUUCCAAAUAUUAUUCUCACCAACCAGAGUGUUAGGGAGGUUACACAAAUAAAAUGUAUAGAACUGAAAAGUGAACUGGGACGGAAGUGGCACAAAGCAUCAAACUACAUCUUCGUGGCCAUCUUCUGGAUUGUGUUUCUUUUGUUAAUCGUUUUCUAUACUGCUAUCACAAAGAAAAUCUUUAAGUCCCACCUUAAGUCAAGUCGGAAUUCCACUUCGGUCAAAAAGAAAUCUAGCCGCAACAUAUUCAGCAUCGUGUUUGUGUUUUUUGUCUGUUUUGUACCUUACCAUAUUGCCAGAAUCCCCUACACAAAGAGUCAGACCGAAGCUCAUUACAGCUGCCAGUCAAAAGAAAUCUUGCGGUAUAUGAAAGAAUUCACUCUGCUACUAUCUGCUGCAAAUGUAUGCUUGGACCCUAUUAUUUAUUUCUUUCUAUGCCAGCCGUUUAGGGAAAUCUUAUGUAAGAAAUUGCACAUUCCAUUAAAAGCUCAGAAUGACCUAGACAUUUCCAGAAUCAAAAGAGGAAAUACAACACUUGAAAGCACAGAUACUUUGUGAGUUCCUACCCUCUUCCAAAGAAAGACCACGUGUGCAUGUUGUCAUCUUCAAUUACAUAACAGAAAUCAAUAAGAUAUGUGCCCUCAUCAUAAAUAUCAUCUCUAGCACUGCCAUCCAAUUUAGUUCAAUAAAAUUCAAAUAUAAGUUUCCAUGCUUUUUUGUAACAUCAAAGAAAACAUACCCAUCAGUAAUUUCUCUAAUACUGACCUUUCUAUUCUCUAUUAAUAAAAAAUUAAUACAUACAAUUAUUCAAUUCUAUUAUAUUAAAAUAAGUUAAAGUUUAUAACCACUAGUCUGGUCAGUUAAUGUAGAAAUUUAAAUAGUAAAUAAAACACAACAUAAUCAAAGACAACUCACUCAGGCAUCUUCUUUCUCUAAAUACCAGAAUCUAGUAUGUAAUUGUUUUCAACACUGUCCUUAAAGACUAACUUGAAAGCAGGCACAGUUUGAUGAAGGGCUAGAGAGCUGUUUGCAAUAAAAAGUCAGGUUUUUUUCCUGAUUUGAAGAAGCAGGAAAAGCUGACACCCAGACAAUCACUUAAGAAACCCCUUAUUGAUGUAUUUCAUGGCACUGCAAAGGAAGAGGAAUAUUAAUUGUAUACUUAGCAAGAAAAUUUUUUUUUUCUGAUAGCACUUUGAGGAUAUUAGAUACAUGCUAAAUAUGUUUUCUACAAAGACUUACGUCAUUUAAUGAGCCUGGGGUUCUGGUGUUAGAAUAUUUUUAAGUAGGCUUUACUGAGAGAAACUAAAUAUUGGCAUACGUUAUCAGCAACUUCCCCUGUUCAAUAGUAUGGGAAAAAUAAGAUGACUGGGAAAAAGACACACCCACACCGUAGAACAUAUAUUAAUCUACUGGCGAAUGGGAAAGGAGACCAUUUUCUUAGAAAGCAAAUAAACUUGAUUUUUUUAAAUCUAAAAUUUACAUUAAUGAGUGCAAAAUAACACAUAAAAUGAAAAUUCACACAUCACAUUUUUCUGGAAAACAGACGGAUUUUACUUCUGGAGACAUGGCAUACGGUUACUGACUUAUGAGCUACCAAAACUAAAUUCUUUCUCUGCUAUUAACUGGCUAGAAGACAUUCAUCUAUUUUUCAAAUGUUCUUUCAAAACAUUUUUAUAAGUAAUGUUUGUAUCUAUUUCAUGCUUUACUGUCUAUAUACUAAUAAAGAAAUGUUUUAAUACUG